AUACCGUCAAAGUUUUCUAAGCAUGAUGUAUGGUCAACAAGAUCAAUAAUAUGAAUCAUCAGUAGAGAUACUAGAUAAGAAGUUGGAAAAGUAUGUUCCUAAAGACUCUCAAAUUUACUCUCAUGGAACAAUCACUAAUAUUUUGUUUAACAGUGGUUUUACUUUAUUAAAAGCAACAUUUCUGUUUUAAUAGUUGGGAUAAUAUUGAAGAGCAGCAUUAGGUGAAAGAUCUAAGGCUUCUCAUAAAUGAUAGUUCUAAAGAAUUAACCCCAGGGCCAAAAACAUUAUGUCCUGUCCUAACCUCUCCAUCCCUUGCUCCUCAUGACACUUUAUUUUUACUGGUUCCCUCUUGACAUUAGAUUAUGCAAUAUAUGGCCAACAUCCACAGCUUUUCUUGUACGCAGCAAACAGUAUCUCAUAUUGCUUUGGGAACAAUAGAGUAAGGGCUUAAAAGCUAUAAGAGUAGAGAUGAAAACUGAAACUGGCCAAGCUACAGCAGAGGCUGGGGGCUGAGAGGAGAUGAAAUCAUGAAAAAAUAAGUGGUACUGAAACAUGACCCAAAUCUUAUGGGGGGUGGAAAAAGGAAAAAAGCCAAAUAAAUGACAGAGAGAAGGAGAAGUGAAUGAUGCAGGGUUGGGCAGUAGGAAAGUGAAGGAAACAAAUAUGAUCAAAUAUGGAAAUAAAGCCACAGCUGAAAGAUAAGGAUGAACUAUAAGCAGUGGGAAAAAGACCUGAUGCAAAGGAUAAAGGAUCCACUGACUUAUUCCUCAAACACUUACUGAUUACUCACUGUGAGCAGGUGUAUUUUUGGACCCUGAGCAUUCAGUAAUGAACCAAACAAAACCCUUACUCUCAUGGAGUUACAUCAUAAAGUCGGGAUGCAGUCAAUACAUAAGAUAAAUGCUGAGGAAAUGGAGUAAAGAGUGCUAGAGAUAGAGAGCGGAAAGGGUUCUGAUUGCAUAUAACCUAGUUCCUUCCUCAGUGAGCGGGAAGCACUGGAGGAAAAGCCUGCAGAAAGGGAGAAAGCAAGCCAUGCAGCUUUCGCAGGUAUUCCAGGCAAGGGGAAUGGCAACUCCACAGCCCUAAGGCAGAUGCAUAUUUGUAAGGGUCAGGGAGAACAGUGUGGGGAAAUGGAAGUAGAAAGACAGCAGGAGAAGAAGCCAAAUGGGCUCAGAACAUGUAGGGUUUGAUAGGCCAUUAUGAGGCUUGAUCUUUCCCACUAAAUAAGAUGAGAAGCUGUGGAAGGAUAUUGAGCACAUGAGUGGCAAUAUCAGUCUAGCUGCUGUGUUAAGAACAGAGUAGAGAGGGGACAAGAGUGGAAACAGAGAAGUUACCAAGGAGCUGACAGUCCAGGGUGGAGAUGAAGGUUGCUUGAACCAAGGUGGCAGCAGUAGAGGUAGAAAACAAUGGUCAGAUUCUGGAUAUAGUUUGAAGACCAACACAAUAGGAUUUCCAGAAGGGUUAGACAUGGGUGUGAGAGAAAGAGAAUAACCAAGGAUAAUUCUAAAAAUUUUGAUCUAGAAAAAUGGAGUUAACAUUUUCUGAAAUCAUGAGGAGAAGCAGGAGCUACAGGAGGAGCAGGUUUGCAGUUGAGGAUCCGGAAUUCAGUUCUGGACACAUUACAUUUGAGAUUGAAUAAGAAGCAUUUCUUAAAAAUGAGGUCCAUGGACCACCUGCUUCUGACUCAGAUGCCUGUUCACAGUAUAGACCCUUGGCUUCACCCCAGAACUAAUCAUGUGAUUCUGAUGCAUACUGAAGUACUGAGAACAAAUUCUCACCAUAGGAAAGGAUUAAAGUUCUGAGAACUUCUGACCUCCUAACAUAAACAAAAUUCCUGGAGCUAGGGGAAAUCUCUGCCAGGCUGUCACCAGAAAUUAUAACAAUGCCACUGACCAACUAUGAUAUCCAGCAUACCACAAAUCUGGCAAACACCCCUACUCAUUUAUUCACUUGGCAAGUAGUUUUUUAGCUCCCUCUCUUUACUAGGCAUUGUUGUGGUAAACAAGACAAAAAUUAGCAAUUUAUUGAGGUAUUUUUAUUUUCCUGCACAGAACUACAUGAAAAGAAUGGAAAUUAAUAGUUAAGCAGAAUCUUCAUAAUCAAAAUUUUGGUUUCAGCAAAUUUCAUGAGGAUUGCAUAUGAUCAGUAAAAUAAGAGGUCCUGAUAUUAAUAAUAGCAUAGUAGGAAACAUAACGUUUAUAUCCCACUACUGGAUGAGAAUUCUCUGAGUUUAGAAACUUCCCUGUUCAAAGGGUAUUGGCACAGGUUAGCUUUGUACUGAAAUGACUAAGCUUCCAGUUGCUGUUUUAUUGCCUGGAGUCAUCAUUGCACACUGCUUCACACAGUGAGCUGGGUGGAAAAAAAUAAAAAUAAAUGUUUUUUAUGGUUACUUUCAAAGUAUUUUCACUUUAGGUCAUAGGCUGAAAUCUGGGCACUUUAGAGGUGAAUAAAUGCUAACCAUGUAUUUAAAAAAAAAUUAAUGGAGAAGUUUAAAUCCAGUUUUAGAAUACCAACCAGAUUUCACUCUCAGAACCUAUCAGACUUUUUCUGCUACUUAGUAACCUAAUAAAAACUUUGCAGUCUAUGCCUCUUCUAAGGGCAGCUCAAAAGGCACGUGUACAAUCCUGUCCUUAGUAAGUUUAAUUAACAUGAUGUAAUAAAUUUUAGCAGAAAGUGCAUUAUUCCAAACAGUUUCUUUUUCCAAGCAUGUUGGCCAGCAACCUUUGUUGAAACAAAGGAACCAGCCACCUGCACUUCUAAGCACAAAUUAAGCACAAAGAGCCAGUGUUCCAGAGGCUGCCUUCUACCUGGCCAGUACAGCCAGAAGGCAAUGUUUGCCCAGGUUUCAUAUACAGGGUCUUCUCCUGAUCAAAGGAAUAGGAGCAAACACUGCAUGCCCCUGUGAGUCCUGAAGGGAACAACUUAAUUCUUUAUUGAAGACCUAUAACAUUUUUUAUGAGAACCAGAAAAAUCUGCAUAUUUUAUAUGGAGAGACUGAAGAUGGCAAACUAAUUGUUGAAGGAAUGCUGGACAUUUUCUGGGGAGUAAAACGACCUAUACAGCUAAAAAUACAAGAUGAGAAGCCAUUCUCUUCUUUUACUAGUAUGAAGUCAUCAGACGUCUUCUCCAGCAAAGGAAUGACACGCUGGGGGGAAUUUGACGAUCUCUAUCGUAUUAGUGAGCUGGACAGGACCCAGAUUCCUAUGUCUGAAAAAAGGAAUUCCCAGGAAGACUAUUUAUCUUAUCACAGCAACACCCUGAAGCCACAUGCAAAGGAUGAACCAGACUCCCCAGUGCUCUAUAGAACCAUGAGUGAAGCAGCUCUGGUGAGAAAAAGGAUGAAGCCUCUGAUGAUGGACAGAAAAGAAAGACAGAAAAAUAGAGCCUCUAUUAAUGGACACUUCUAUAACCAUGAAACAUCAAUUUUCAUUCCAGCCUUUGAAUCAGAAACUAAGGUCAGAGUAAACAGUAACAUGAGAACUGAAGAAGUAAUAAAGCAACUUCUCCAAAAAUUUAAGAUUGAAAAUAGUCCCCAGGAUUUUGCUCUUCACAUUAUUUUUGCAACAGGAGAACAAAGACGACUAAAGAAGACAGACAUUCCGCUACUGCAGAGGCUCCUACAGGGACCUUCUGAAAAGAAUGCUCGCAUUUUCCUCAUGGAUAAAGAUGCAGAAGAAAUUAGCAGUGAUGUGGCUCAGUACAUUAACUUUCACUUUUCUCUCUUGGAAUCCAUUCUUCAAAGAUUAAAUGAAGAAGAGAAAAGAGAGAUUCAAAGAAUAGUAACAAAAUUCAAUAAAGAAAAGGCGAUUAUACUGAAAUGUCUUCAAAAUAAACUAGUAAUAAAAACAGAGACAACAGUUUAGCAGUACAAGCUUCUAUUGCUAAAACAUUUCAAAAAACUCAGAGAUAUUACUCUUUGAUGAAUGCAUAAGUUCUGUACUUGCAUUUAUACGAACAUAUAUGAGACUUGAAUCGUAGAAAAUUGAAUGUCAAAAAAAGCUCAUUUCUUUUUGAAGUGAUGAGGUUAAUUAGGGUUCACAGUUGGACAAAAUGAGUUUGAGUUUAGUUUCAGUAACUGAAAUAAGCUUGAAUACUGCAUAUGCCAAAUAGCUUUUAUAGUAAACCAUGUAAUGAACUCAAAUUUAAAUGGUGUCUUCAGAUAAGCAGUUUAAACUUCAUUUAGCUUGGACUCUCAAGAGAACUGAAACAUAAUCAAUGGAUUCAGAAAUGACUCAGAAAAAAGAAGCUGCCAGUUCUUGGAAUGAAAAAGAAAUACAGUCUUACACCAUCAAGGAAUCUACCUGAUAGUGACAGUAGCUUCUUGAAAACUCUGGCAUUUUCAUAAAAUCUAGGACUAUCUUAAAUGGCCUGUUGACUUCUGACUAUCUGUAACAUCAGAGCUGUCUGGCCUUUGGAAAGGAAAAAUUAUGGACUCUGUUAAGAAAUCCUAAUUGAAAUUUUCUGAACCUCCCCCCAGCCCUUUUAUUCUCUCUCUUCUGCUGAUGAAAGACCUUUCAUCAGUUCAAAGCUUUUCUUAAGCUCUUUUUUAAGUUAAUUGAACUUUUUCUUUAUUUAUUUUUCAAAAAAAUGUUUAUAUCACAUAGACAUAUUACAUCGGCUAAAGUAAGACUUGGCCCACAAAUACCUAUUUGUUGCUGAAUGAAUACAAUGGAUAAAGCAAGGCUGUUGUAGCUGAAGUUACAUAGGGAAUCCCAAACUCUGCCCUCUUAGCAUCUUAUUCUACAUGACAACUCUCAAGGUACUCACAGAUCUGUUUAACCCACUUGAAAAAAAAACACUAAAAAUGAAGAAAUGCUAUAAGUAUAAACUAUGAUUUUAUUUAUAAAUUCUGUAUUAAAAUGGAAUUAUAUGCAACAUUCUUUCAUUCUGUAAACUAAUUCCAUUUGCAUUCCUCAUAAGCAUUGUAGUAAAUUGAUCAUAUUACAUGUACUAAGGAAUGAGAUUAUAUGCAGUAAACCCAACUGGAAGAUUAACAAUAUUAAAAUAUGAAACAUUUUUAAGACAAAGGCAUUACUUCUCAGUAUUACCAAACCUAAACUGGUUGAAGGUGAAAGUGUGCUAUGGCCUUUUCAAGCCUAAGAAGUCUCUCUUACUGAGUAAACCAGAGGCUUGCAUCGCUAUUCUUUCACCUGUCAAUAUUAAUAAGAAAAUAGUCUCAUCUCACUUAAAUGAGGCAAAUGUAAUAGUUAAAAUUCAACAUACUUAUAAAAAACUAGUGUCAUGUACCUGCCAUGAACAUGACAAAAGGUUAGUCUUCAAUAGACUGAAAUGUAUAAGAGAAGAACCAAGUCUUACAUAGAAAAAAAAGGUAGAUAUGAAAAGAAAAAUCACAGAAGAGAGAAUGCAAAUGGCCACUAAGUAUAUGAAAAAAGUCGUAUCUUAACAGUGAACAACUGUGUUAGUCUGUAUCAAUCAGAAGACAGAAACAAGGUAGUAAUUUAAACAGGGAAAGUUUAAUAUAAAUAAUAAUUAAGCUAUGAUAGGAGAAUAAUAAUAAAGAUGAAAAGAGAAGGUACCCUAAGGCUGAGGGAAAGAAUCCUAACAAGGAAAGGCAGGAAUGAGGGUUUCAGAAUUCACUGGAGAAGGUGUGGUUGCAGCCCACUGGAGAGAAGUUUGCUGGCUUGCCCAGGCCAGAGCAGGACCACAGAUACUGGACAAGCUGGUACAGCCAACCCCCUAGGUGUGGACCAGCUGAGGCAGGUGGGCAGAUAUGCAGAGGGACUUGGGGCUUUGCCAAAGGGUAAGCACAAAGAAGGAGUCACGGGUUCUGUUCGAGGCACUGUUGGGAUUAGGAGCCGGAGGGACCUACUUUGCAGGAACCUAGCAUAACUUUGUGUGACGAGACUGCACAAGACAAAGCUCAGGCAAGUGGCUCAGUAGUUGGCCAGCCCAGCAGGGUCCUCUGUAUGAGUGUGCACCCAGCUGAAGAGAAGAAAUGGAGAGCAGCAAUUGGAGCUUCAGGACCGGCUUGCACUGUGGCUCCAGGUUAUACCACCACUGCCCAAAGCAAAAGCUAGAGAAGCAAGUGGAGAAAUGCUGGAGAAAGCUGCACCCUACAGGCAACCAGCACUGCAGAAACCACUCCAGGCAAAGUAGUGAAGGAAAAAAGCCUGCUCUCCAGUAGCCUGGCCUGUCAGCCUGGAGGAAUCAGGAAAGACCCCUUCCUCUUGCAGUGUGUCUCCAGCGCCCUCUACUGACAAAGUAUGCCAUCAUGCAAGCUGCAAAGGAAACAUUUCAAGAGUCUAUAUCUAUUUUCACGGAGCGGGCAACCAACAGUGAAUGUGGAGCUGAGAGACAGUAAAAUAAUAACUGACAUGCCACCGAAGUACAAAGUAAAAUAAAUAAAUAAAUACACAUUUUGGCCUAUUAGCAAAGAUUAAGAAAUGAUAACAUUAAAUACUCAAUAAAUCACCAUGAGAUGGGGACUCAAACUUCUGGUAAAAAUACAAAUAGAUAUAAUUUUUCUUGAAGGCAAUUUAGUAGUCUGUUUAUCCUAUAAUUCUACUUGUAAGAUCCUAUCAUAUGAAAAUAACCAGAGAUACAAAGACAUUCUGCAAAGAUAUGUUUUAUAUUGUUAUUUAUUGUGACAAAAGGAAAUAAAAAGCCUAAAUGUUCAGAAAAUUAUUUUAAAAGAUGAAAGAGGGAAAUAGGCCAUGGACGGUGGCUCACGCCUGUAAUCCCAGCACUUUAGGAGGCCAAGGUAGGUGGAUCACUUGAGGUUGGGAUUUCGAGACCAGCCUGGCCAACAUGGUGAAACCCUGCCUCUACUAAAAAUACAAAAAAUGAGCCGGGUGCAAUGGCAGGCACCUAUAAUGCCAGCUACUCGGGAGGCUGAGGCAGGAGAAUCGCUUGAACCCGGGAGGCGGAGGUUGCAUGAGCCGAGAUGGCGCCACUGCUCUCCAGCCUGGACGACAGAGCAAGACUCCGUCUCUAAAAAAAAAAAAAGAGGGAAAUAAACAUUUAUUUGUAUAUUGUUAUGUAGCCAUUAAAAUUCUGUUUCCAAGUAAUUUUAAUUACAGGGGUAAAUUCUUAUAUAUCUAAAUAAGAAUAUACACAUACACAUGUUCCAAAAUAUUUAUUAUGUACUUAAGGCAUAUAUAUUAUAUAUGUAUGUGUGUGUAUAUAUAUAUGUAUUUGUGUGUGUGAACACUAAUAUUUGCAUAUAUAUACACACAAGAAAUAAAAACAUGUUAAAAAUGGCUAUAUCUGCAUUGUAGAAUUAUGAGUGAUUCAUGUUUUUCUAACUUCCCUAUCUGUAUUAAGUGUUCUAUAGUUUAUAUUUGUUACUUUUUACAUCAGGAAAUAGUAAAGUUAUUAUUUAAAACUUAUGAACAAAAAAGUAACAAGCACAUGCAAGCACAGAGUUCUACCAAAUGCAAAAAAUUUCAAAUCAAUUAUUCAAAUGAGACAUUAACAUCACUUCUGUGGUAGUUUUAUAUCCAUAAAGUCUGAUUCUUCUCCUUUGAAGAGAUGAAGCUUAAUCUUCCUCAUCCUGAAAAUGGGCUGGACUUAGUGACUUACGUCUUUUUAUUUUAUUUUUAAUUGACAAAUAAUAAUUGUAUGUAUUUAUGGGGUACAAUAUUAUAUUAUUAUAUAUGUAUACAUUAUGGAAUUAUUAAAUCAAGCUAAUUAACAUAUCCAUAACCUCUUAUAAUUUCUUUGUGGUGAGAACAUUUAAAAAUGUACUCUUUUAGCAAUUAGGGACUUACUUUUAAUACAGGAAAAUGGAAGAGACUGUGAGACUUUGAAGUAGGUCAUAAAAGUCACUGUGGCUUCCUCCUUGCUCUCUCUUGGACCACUUGCUCUGGGGGAAGUCAACUGCCAUGUCCUGAGCAGCCCUGGAAAGACCUACAUGAUGAAGAACUGAGACCUUCUAUCAAAUGCCAGCAGGGAAUUGAGGCCUCCUGUCAACAGCCAUUUUAGAAGUAGAUCUUCCAGCCUCAGUCAAGCCUUCAGAUGACUGCAGCCCUGUCUAAUAGCUUGACCGUAAUUUCAUGAGAGACCUUCAGCCAGAAAACCCAAGGAAACCAUUCUGGAUUCCUCAUCCUCAGAAACUGUAUGAGAUAAGAAGUGUUUGUUGUAGUACGCCGCUAAAUUUGGGGCAAUUUGUUACAUAGCAAUGUAUAGCUCAUACAAUUUCUGGGAAAAAAAUAGUUUAUUUUCGAAUCAUUUUUGCAUAAUGCAAGAAUAUAAACUUGUCACAGAAUAAUUUAUCCUUGUUUUAGGUGGUCCAAAUAUUUCAUUGUCAGUUAUAUAUUAGCUCAAAUUAAAUUUUAGAUAAUAUAUAUUAUUAUUAAUGGUAAAGAAUGUGUCACAUUUAUCUUUAUAGCUUUUCUGUACCUAAUAUUGUGUCUUGUGCGUAGGAUGUGCUCAAUAAAAAUUGAUUGAAUAAAUAAGUGAAUGAAAGAAUAAAUGAAUGAGUGAAGGAAUUAUCUGAAAUAUUUUUAUAAAAUUCCCCAUAUGUAUGUAUUACUUAUUACAAGUCUGGUCCCAUAGCUGAAAAAAUAUUAAACAUUAUAUAUAUAUA